GGGAUUUUGGAGUUGAGCACCAUGGGGACUCCAAAUGAUCAGGCAGUGCUGCAGGCCAUCUUCAACCCUGACACCCCAUUUGGAGACAUUGUUGGAUUGGACCUCGGAGAGGAAGCAGAAAAGGAAGAACGAGAAGAAGAGAAUACCACCACCAGAACAGAAGACUGAAAUAAGGCAGGGCAUGGUUGCUCAGUUGAGUGGUUCCAAUAUAGCAAGCACAACCAGUAACCGUUAAACACUGUCACAAGCCAAGCUCCAAACUAACUCUUCCGCAAUGAAGUUUUCCCUCAAGCACAGCUGGAACAGUCCAAGGCCCUGGAGCUGCAGGGGGUGAUGGCAGCAGAGGCUGGGGACCUCAGCACAGCCCUGGAGAGGUUUGGCCAAGCCAUCUGCCUGCUGCCUGAGAGGGCUUCAGCCUACAACAACCGUGCCCAGGCCCGGCGACUCCAGGGAGACGUGGCAGGCGCCCUGGAGGAUCUGGAACGCGCGGUGGAGCUGAGCGGCGGCCGGGGCCGCGCCGCCCGCCAGAGCUUUGUGCAGCGCGGACUCCUGGCGCGGCUGCAGGGCCGAGACGACGACGCCCGCAGGGACUUCGAGAGGGCGGCACGGCUGGGCAGCCCCUUCGCGCGGCGCCAGCUGGUGCUGCUCAACCCCUACGCCGCGCUGUGCAACCGCAUGCUGGCCGACAUGAUGGGGCAGCUGCGCCGCCCCCGUGACAGCCGCUGAGCGCCGCGGACCCGGGCGUCCGCGGGCGAGGGGACGGGACUGGGCCCUGAACCAAUAAAGCCGUCGGGCCUCACCGA